ACACCCGCCUCCUAGCAACCGGAGCUCAGGUUCAGCCUAGAGAGAGAGGAGGCCACCAUGGACCAGCCAGCCGUCGCCACCGCUUCCACCUCAAUAAGGGAAGACCUGGUGGGUGGAGAAUCAUUCAUCACAGCUUCGAAACCAGCCCAAAAGACUUCCUCUUUUGAAAGAGAAGGAUGGUGGAGAAUAGCAUUAACAGAUACUCCUAUACCUGGCACUUACCACUUGAAAACUUUUAUUGAAGAAUCCCUAUUAAAUCCAGUGAUAGCAACCUACAAUUUUAAAAACGAAGGAAGGAAAAAGCCACCUCUUGUGCAAAGAAACAAUCCAGUCCUAAAUGAUCUUCCGCAGUAUAUGCCUCCUGACUUCCUGGACCUGUUAAAGAAGCAAGUGGCUACUUACUCAUUCAAAGACAAACCACGGCCAAGCCCCAGCACACUAGUUGACAAAGAUCAGUCACUUCAGCUUUCUCCGGGGCAAUACAACGUGCUUCCUGCACCAGUUCCCAAAUAUGCUUCCAGGAGCUGUGUAUUUCGCUCAACAGUUCAAAGAUUCCCAACAACCUAUUUUAUUCCCGUAAGUAUAAUGUAGACAGUUAACUCAUGAUGAAUUUGAUGUUUAAAAUACGCUGUGCUUUCUGGAGUGGAGCAAGGUGGCCACAUAGAACCCUCCAGUGAUCGUUCCCCCUAGCAGGAACACCAUUAUCCACACAAUUAUCCACACAAGAAAACACCUCUGUAAGAACCAAAAAGCAAGUGUGGGAUCGCAAUACCAGGUUUUAACAUUGUAUCAAGGAAAGAGGCACUGAAGAGGGUAGGGUAGAAAAGACAGUCUUGAAUUACUGACACUACCCUCCCCCAUCCCCUGGCAGCAGCCACGUGGCAUGAAGAGAGAAUCUGCCCUUGGGGAAGAGGGAAUGCCGUGACGGGGGGACUUUGCACGGGAACACCGUGCUGCCUGUAACAGGGAAAGCAACACAGGACAGAAUUCAGCUAGUGCCCAUGGAGGGAGCAUUUAGACCAGCACUAGCCAGCCAGGAAUUGCCCAUCCCAGCCGUUCGAUACUGAGUUCCAGCUCUCCCUACCACUGUGGGCUGAAGUGCUCUGAGGUCCUAAAUAAGCUUGAAAGGCAGUCUCGGCCACAAGGACUGCAGUUCCUGGGCAAGUUCAGGUGCUCUGCUGGGCUCAGAGGCAGUGGACUUAGGGUACACAAGACCUAGUGAGACACCAGCUGGGGCAGCCAAAGGAGUGCUUGUAGCAGCCAUCCCCCAGCCCCAGGCAGCACAGCUUGCAGCUUCAAGAGAGAGGCCUUCCUUUUGCUUGAGAGGAGGAGAGGGGAGAGUAAAGAGGACUUGUCUUGAAUCUGGAUACCAGCUCAGCCACAGCAGAAUAGGGCACCUCAGGCAGAGUCCUGAGGCCCCCAUACCAGGCCCUAGCUCCCAGACAACAUUUCUAGACACAUCUCUGGCUGGAAGAGAAUCCACUGCCUUAAAGAGAAGGACCCAGUUCUGGCAAGAUUCAUCACCUACUGACUAAAGAGCCCUUGGGCUUCGAAUAAACACCAGCAGUGGCCAGACAACACUCACUGCAGGCCUUAGCCAGUGCUGUGCUGCUUCAGGUGUGAUCCAGCACUUUCCCAGCUACAGUGGUCACAGAGAGAGACUCCUGCUUGAGGAAAGGAGAGGGAGGAGUAAAGGGGAUUUUGUCUUGCAGCUUGGGUACCAGUUCGGCCACAGUGAAGUGGAGCACCAAGCAGGCUCCUGGGGUUCCCAAUUCCAGGCAUUGGCUCCUGGAUGUCAUUUCUGGACUCCCACUGGGCCAGAGGGGAGCCCACUGCCCUGAAGGGAGAGACCCAGGCCUGGCAGCCUUCCUCACAAGCUGACUGAAGAGCCUUGAGUGAACAUUAGUGGUAUCCAGGCAGUACUUGCUACAGGCCUGAGUGGCAUAGAGAGAUUCUUUCUGCUUGAGGAGAGGGGAGGGACGAGUGGAAAAACUUUGUCUUCUGGCUUGGGUGCCAGCUUAGCUGCAGUAGUAUAGAGUACCCAAUAAAUUCCUAAGUUUCCUGACUCC